AGCCUGGAAGGGAAAGGACAGCGGAGAGCAGGGCAGAGCCUGAGCAGGCAGGUAAGGAGAUCCGGGUCAGGAGAGAAGGGGGCCGGGGCUUGACCAAUGGGUCUGAGGGACGGGGGGACUGGGGUCUGGACUCCAGGGUCUCAGGGAGGACGGGCUGGGGGUCUGAACUCCCGGGUCUGAGGGAGGAGGGCCUGGGGUCCUGGACUCCUAGGUCUGAGGGAGGAGGGGCUGAGGGCCUGGACUCCUGGGUCUGAGGGAGGAGGAGAUGGGGCCUGGACUCCUGGGUCUGAGGGAGGAGUGGACUGGGGUCUGGACUCCUGGGUCUGAGGGAGGAGGGGACUGGGGUCUGGACUCCUGGGUCUAGGGAAGAGGGACUGGGGCCUGGACUUCUGGGUCUGAGGGAGGAGGGGCUGGGGGCCUGGACUCCUGGGCCUGAGGGAGGAGGGGCUGGGGCCUGGAUGCCUGCAUUGAGGGAGGAGGCUGGGGUAGGAAUUAGAGGCUCCUACUGGCCAGGCCUUCACAUGUUUGCUGGCUCCCAGGGCACCUCCAGGUGGGCAGGAGCUACCACUCAGCACCAUGAGCACCGCCACAGGCCCAGAAGCUGCCCCAAAGCCAAGCGCCAAGUCUAUCUAUGAGCAGAGGAAGCGUUACUCCACAGUUGUUAUGGCUGAUGUAUCCCAGUACCCAGUCAAUCACCUGGUGACGUUCUGCCUGGGUGAGGACGAUGGCGUGCAUACCGUGGAGGAUGCCUCCAGGAAGUUGGCCGUCAUGGAUAGCCAGGGCCGAGUCUGGGCACAGGAGAUGCUGCUGCGAGUGUCUCCCGACCAUGUCACGCUGCUCGACCCGGCCUCCAAGGAGGAGCUGGAGUCGUACCCACUGGGCGCCAUCGUGCGCUGUGACGCGGUGAUGCCACCCGGCAGGAGCCGCUCGUUGCUGCUGCUCGUGUGCCAGGAACCCGAGCGCGCGCAGCCCGACGUGCACUUCUUCCAGGGCCUGCGCCUCGGGGCGGAGCUGAUCCGAGAGGACAUCCAGGGGGCUCUGCACAAUUACCGCUCGGGCCGCGGGGAGCGCAGGGCGGCGGCGCUCAGGGCCACGCAGGAGGAGUUGCAGCGCGACCGCUCGCCCGCCGCUGAGACCCCGCCCCUGCAGCGCCGCCCGUCAGUCCGCGCAGUGAUCAGCACCGUAGAGCGGGGCGCGGGCCGCGGACGACCCCAGGCGAAGCCCAUUCCCGAGGCAGAGGAGGCGCAGAGGCCUGAGCCGGUGGGGACCUCGAGCAACGCUGACUCGGCCUCCCCGGACCUGGGUCCCCGGGGUCCUGACCUGGCGGUUCUGCAGGCGGAGCGGGAAGUGGACAUCCUGAACCACGUGUUCGACGACGUAGAGAGCUUUGUAUCGAGGCUGCAGAAGUCGGCGGAGGCGGCCAGGGUGCUGGAGCACCGGGAACGCGGCCGCAGGAGCCGGCGCCGGGCGGCUGGGGAGGGCUUGCUGACGCUGCGGGCCAAGCCGCCCUCGGAGGCCGAGUACACCGACGUGCUGCAGAAGAUCAAGUACGCCUUCAGCCUGCUGGCCCGGCUGCGCGGCAACAUCGCCGACCCCUCCUCUCCGGAGCUGUUGCACUUCCUUUUCGGGCCUCUGCAGAUGAUUGUGAACACGUCGGGGGGGCCGGAGUUCGCGAGCAGUGUGCGGCGGCCGCAUCUGACAUCGGAUGCCGUGGCGCUGCUGCGGGACAACGUCACUCCACGUGAAAACGAGCUCUGGACCUCGCUGGGGGACUCGUGGACCCGCCCCGGGCUGGAGCUGUCCCCGGAGGAGGGACCCCCAUACAGACCCGAGUUCUUCAGCGGCUGGGAGCCGCCGGUCACUGACCCGCAGAGCCGCGCCUGGGAGGACCCAGUUGAGAAACAGCUACAGCACGAGCGGAGGCGCCGGCAGCAAAGCGCCCCCCAGGUCGCUGUCAAUGGUCACCGAGACUUGGAGCCAGAAUCUGAGCCUCAGCUGGAGUCAGAGACAGCAGGAAAAUGGGUCCUGUGUAAUUAUGACUUCCAGGCCCGCAACAGCAGUGAGCUGUCGGUCAAGCAGCGGGACGUACUGGAGGUCCUGGAUGACAGUCGUAAGUGGUGGAAGGUUCGGGACCCAGCGGGGCAGGAGGGAUAUGUGCCCUACAACAUCCUGACACCCUACCCCGGACCCCGGCUGCACCACAGCCAAAGCCCUGCCCGCAGCCUGAACAGCACUCCUCCUCCACCACCAGCCCCAGCCCCGGCCCCACCUCCAGCUCUGGCUCGGCCCCGCUGGGACAGGCCCCGCUGGGACAGCUGCGAUAGCCUCAACGGCUUGGACCCCAGCGAGAAGGAGAAAUUCUCCCAGAUGCUCAUCGUCAACGAGGAACUGCAGGCGCGCCUGGCCCAGGGCCGCUCGGGACCGAGCCGCGCAGUCCCAGGGCCCCGCGCCCCGGAACCGCAGCUCAGCCCGGGCUCGGACGCCUCCGAGGUCCGCGCCUGGCUGCAGGCCAAGGGCUUUAGCUCCGGGACCGUGGACGCGCUGGGUGUGCUGACCGGGGCGCAGCUUUUCUCGCUGCAGAAGGAGGAGCUGCGGGCGGUGAGCCCCGAGGAGGGGGCACGUGUGUACAGCCAGGUCACCGUGCAGCGCUCGCUGCUGGAGGACAAAGAGAAAGUGUCAGAGCUGGAGGCAGUGAUGGAGAAGCAAAAGAAGAAGGUGGAAGGCGAGGUGGAAAUGGAGGUCAUUUGACCUGCCAGGCGCCCUUCGCAAAGAGUGACGAGGCCCCGUGGGAGAACGGACUCCUCAGACUCUCCCCAAUAGCGGAAGUCGAUCUUCUGAAGGAUGGCCAAUCUGCUCCGGCCCUGGUCUUCCCCCAUCCCGGUGGACAGACUUAACGAUCCUUGCUGCAGUCCCUCCGGAGAGGAUCUGGACUGGCUGGGAGUGGGGAGGGCGUGGAGACAGUCUACGGAAAGCGCUAGCAGACCCCCGAGAGGGUGCAGUGGAGCCCUGAGCAUUGUAAUAUGCGGCCCAGCCUAUAAACAGCCUCCGUGCUUAGCA